UAGUACUGAAUCACAAGCUGUUUUUCCCUAUACAUACAUAUCUAUGAGAAAGUUUAAUUUAUAAAUUAAAUUAAAUCUGAUGUUAUCUGUAGAUAGGGUGUGAGAAUUGAAUUGUGUCAUCAGCAGGAAUGAUUGCUUGUUUGUUGGUGGGGAAAAACUCUCCACACAUUUGGUCACAGAAGCCUUCUUUGUUGAUGAUUGUUGCUGUGGUGUGACAGCAGAGAAAAACGUGUCAAGUAUGUCUUUCUGCGCAUAUAGUGGAUAAGGGGUACUAGUGUAUACUCUGUUGUAAUGGCCCCUCAUAUUUUGGUCCAGAAAUCAUGCUCUUUGACACUGUUGACUCAUCACACCUGUUCUGCUAACAAUACCAUUUUUACUCAAUCUCAUAGGCUUUGGCUAGGAUGACUUGUAUACUGCAGUUCACUUGUAGAUACCAAAUUUUAAUAAAUUUAUUCUUCUUUGCAUCUAAUAAAUACAGAGGGAAGAGUUCUUACUGCAUUAAUUACCUACCAAUACGUAUAAUGAAUGUUAAUUCUAAUAAGGUCGCAGGCAUGCUCCCAAAGGAAUGCUUUGUAACAAAGCGUCAGUCUUAUGCUUUAAAAAACCAAACCAAACCAAAACAACAACAACAACAACAACAAAAACAGGAUCUAAAGCAUACACACAAGUGUGCACAAUUUUUUUAUGAAGGUAGAGUCUUACUAUGUUUCCCAAGCUGGUCUCAAACUUCUGGGCUCCUCAAGUGAUCCUCCUGCCUCAUCCUCCCAAGUAGUUUGGAUUAGAGGCAUGCAUCACUGUGCAUUCUUAUGAUUUUAAUAUUCUGUACAUUUAUUAUUGAUUUAAAAUGCAUUUUACCUUUUUCUUUAAUAGAUGUUGGAAUUCCUGAUGAAUCUGCAGUCAGCAUUUUGCAUGAACUGUGUGUGGAUUCAUUGCCUACAUUGGAUGAUGAAGACUUGAGUGUUGCUACUAAGCAGUGUGUCCCCCAGAAAGUGUCAGAGCCUUUACGUGGACCUUCUCAUGAAAACGGAAACAGAAUAGUCAAUGGAAAAGGAGAAGAACAAACCUUACCAGUGGCUUUAGAGGAAGAGCAAGAAAGGUGUGAAAGAAGUGAAAAGAAGCAAUCACAGGUCAAAGAAGGAAAUAAUACAAACAAAAGUGAAAAAAUACAACUAUCAGAAAAUGUAUGUCAUAGUACAUCUGCUGCUGCUGCUGACAGAUUAACCCAACAAAGAAAUAUUGGGAAAACCUAUCCUCAGCCUUUUACCAAGAAGCUGAAGGAAGAGCAUCAUAGAUGCAUCUUAAGAUAAGAAAAUAAAGAAAAAACAAAUGU